CCGCUUCCGCUGGCGGGGUCUCCUCCGUGAGCUCCGGGCCUGUUUGCCUGCUGAAGUAGAGUCUUAGGGUGACCCCAGGGGGACGUAAUGUUUCCGAGAAGAAGGACAGAAAGAAGACUGGGAGACACCGGAACUCGAAAGAAAAUCGGUAACAAAAUCAUACAGAAAGGCUGUACCUGGAGGAAGGAAGUGCGGAGCCAGCCUGAGUUGGGAGAAGAGCUCCAGAGAGUGUGAAUGACAGAGGUGGUGCCAUCCAGCGCGCUCAGCGAGGUCAGCCUGCGCCUCCUCUGCCACGAUGACAUAGACACUGUGAAGCACCUGUGUGGCGACUGGUUCCCCAUCGAGUACCCAGACUCAUGGUAUCGUGAUAUCACAUCCAACAAGAAGUUCUUUUCCCUUGCUGCAACCUACAGAGGUGCCAUUGUGGGAAUGAUAGUAGCUGAAAUUAAGAACAGGACCAAAAUACAUAAAGAGGAUGGAGAUAUUCUAGCAUCCAACUUCUCUGUUGACACACAAGUCGCGUACAUCCUAAGUCUGGGCGUCGUGAAAGAGUUCAGGAAGCACGGCAUAGGUUCCCUCUUACUUGAAAGUUUAAAGGAUCACAUAUCAACCACCGCCCAGGACCACUGCAAAGCCAUUUACCUGCAUGUCCUCACCACCAACAACACAGCAAUAAACUUCUAUGAAAACAGAGACUUCAAGCAGCACCACUAUCUCCCCUAUUACUACUCCAUUCGAGGGGUCCUCAAAGAUGGCUUCACCUAUGUCCUCUACAUCAACGGCGGCCACCCUCCCUGGACGAUUUUGGACUACAUCCAGCACCUGGGCUCUGCACUAGCCAGCCUGAGCCCCUGCUCCAUUCCGCACAGAGUCUACCGCCAGGCCCACAGCCUGCUCUGCAGCUUCCUGCCAUGGUCGGGCAUCUCUUCCAAGAGUGGCAUCGAGUACAGCCGGACCAUGUGAUGUCGGCUGGGCAGCCGCCACCAGGCCCCACCCUUCGGCCGCCCGCAGAGCCCGCCUUCCUGUCCAUCUGACCCCUUCUGUUUUCUGCAAGGAGCUGCCAGCCAUCUAACUGGGCUCGUCGGCCUGCCCCAGCUGCAGGCCCGGUGCUACACGGGCUCGGGAACAGAACAUCGUGGGCAUGCGCAGAGCAUGCCCAUCCGUGGCAGGCUCUUCAGCUCCCCUCCCUGCUUCUGGAAACCUCUGCCUGCUGCCCUGGCCCUGCCCCCCUGCGCAUGCACCGUCCCCAGGGCUGACCCAGUGUGGCUGCAUUCACUGGGAGGGGCCUGCCCUCACUGGGCCUCUCCCACUCCGCUGCCUGUUCUUGCAGCUCCUUCCUGGAAAGCUGGAGGGGACUUUCUCCUGCAAGGGAGGAACGCAAGUAUUAUGGACACACUUGACCGUAAAGGCACAGGAGCCUCGGAACAAGGGGGCGCAAUAAAGGGAAUGGCCCGUCCCCUUCCAGAACCAGCCCAAAGAAGCCUGGGGGGUGAGGAGUGGCCCCCACUCCUCCAUGAGGGGCUGAUGAGGGGUGGGCAGCCUGGGGGAGGCUUUCCUCGCAAGCACAGAGCUCUGAGGCUCAGCCCCCUGGCACAGGCGGUCACGCAUCAGGACGGUUCCUACUCCUCAGCACCUUCCGUGCAGUUACCAGUGCCCUGGGAGGUCACACUGCCCGUCGGACCUUGGCAUGCUCCAUUCAGCUGACCUGCUGAGGACAGGCAUCGCCGAGACUCCUUGGGUCCUCCCCGCCCUCCCUCAUGCUGCCACAAGCUGCUGCUCCAAGGCCUGGCCACAUGCAGACAGGAGGAAGCUGAGCUCGACAUUAGGCCUCAAGGCUGCCAUCUGUCUUGUAGGGCCUGGCCUUGUGGGCAGGGGGCAGUCCUGUGCCUUGUGGGCCCUCAGCCUCUGAGGGCAGAGAUGCUGUCAGUGCCGCAGGUGCAUCACAUACUUCUAGCAUCCUCUCCACCCUGCAUUCCAAAUGCUGCUUGCUGCCUGCCCUGCCCUCCGAUGCAGGGGUGGGGUGGGGGGCGGAGUCCCGCCCAGCAUAGCUGCAGUGUCACAAAGCCAUGGCAGAGGGUCCUAGCGGCGCCACCCUGCCCCAGCCUGAGGAGGAGGGAGAGGGAGGAACAACCCUGGGCAGACGGGGCCUCAGGGACCUGUGUCCUUCCGCCUCCAGAGCUGCCCAGCCACGGGCUCUCAGGGUGCUGGGGCAGCCCCAGGUCCCCUCUUGAACUCAGCUGGGGCCAGGGGCCCUCAGAAUGAAGGCAGGCACCAGGCAGGAGCAGCAUCCCCCUCCUUGACGGUGCUGGCAGGAGGGCCGCGCCAUGCUGACUGCUUGAACCUCUGCUGACCUGACAGUGCUGGCGGGAGGGCCGCACCAUGCUGACUGCCUGAAUCUCUGCUGAGGCUGCCUGCCUGCCGGGCCCAGCUCAGCGCCCUCUCCACUGCGAAUCAGUGGCGAUCAUGUGAUUUCUAUUUCUGCCCCACAGGGUAAGGGACGAGUCUUCUGGAAGGCUCUGCCAUGGACAUUUGUCCUCGGGCUCAGAGGCCCCACCCUGCCCCACACCUGCCCCUGAUCACUGCAGUGUCCAGCCCAGUGUUGAACAGAUUGUAGCGUUCUGUCUCAUUACGAGCAAAUAAAUAGACUUUCAUUGGA